CUUUCUGAUAGCAGGCAGCCAUCUUGCCUGGAGCCUGAGAAAGGGAGGAGAGACAGAAGGAACCGGCGACAGUGGUCUCAGGGCCGCUCCGGGGGGCCUCAAGAACCGGAGGCAGCCCCGGAGGUGGUCCCCGAUCCCGGGCUAUGCUCUUGGAUCUGAGAAGGGAAGGCGGAGGGCGGCGGGGACAAGAUGGGUGGAGAAUGUCAAGCAAGGAAUGCUAGGCGGGGGAGGGGCGUUGCUAUGGCGACUGGGGAGGGGCGGUGUCUGUUCUGAAUCGCUGUGUGUCACCCGGGCGCUGCCCAGGAAGGGCAGGGCUGGGGUGAUGACCAUGGUAACACCCGGGGGGGAGUUCGUGACAUCUCCGGCGCGGAGGGACUCGAUGUCUAUGGCAAUGGUCGCCUGGUGGAAGGGACGGAACUAGAUCCCUUCGCUCGGGACGCUCACAUUCCAGGCCCUUGUCCUGCAGGCUGCCGCGGGCGGACACGCCAGAGGAGGAGGCCGGGGAAUGGCCGCGGUGUGGCAGCAAGUCUUAGCAGUGGACGCGAGGUGAGGCGUGGGGUCAAAGCCCAUGGGAGCAGAACUUACUGUGGUGCAUGCGCAAUGGCGAUAAGUGAGGCUGGGCGGAGAACUUGCCUUAUGCGGCUGCGUGGGCAUGCCGGAGGUGAGCAUGCGCAGUAGCGGGGGCGGGCACGCCCGCGGUGAGUUGGCUGCGCCGGAGAGGAUUCUAAACAGCAAGCUGGGAAAAUGUGGUCAGAUGUGGGCAUGCGCAAAGCGGCUACCUGUGAGAGGGAGGUGGGGCUCAGGCAGGUGACAUCCUAUCCCCUAUGGGUGUCCCCUAGACUUUUUUUUUUUUACAUCAUCACUUCCCCAUUCUGACCCCAUCACCUCCCAACGCUGACCCCCAUAAUGUCAGUCUGAUUUCUGUCGCCCUGGUAUACUGACCCUAAUUAUUGUCUGCGCUGACCCAGUCACCCCGUAGGGACCCCAGCACGGCAGCAGACUGACUCUGUUGUCUGCAAACUGACCUCAUGACCAUGCUCAUUAUUACUGCAGACUCACUCCCACCACAGGACCAAGAGGUCCCUCAUCACCACUGCUAGUCAUUCUUACCACCUAGGCCCCAGUCACUGCCACACACCUCACUCUCCUGCCGUACCCCCCCCCCCGAGCUGAUUGAUUCCCUCUGUCCUGUGCCUGCUGCCUGCCCUGCAUCCUGACCCUGCAGGUACAACGCGUACCGCACACCAACGUUUCCACAGUUUCGGACGCAGUAUAUCCGCCGGCGCAGCCAGCUGCUGCGGGAGAAUGCCAAGGCUGGGCACCCCCCAGCGCUGCGUCGGCAGUACCUGAGGCUUCGGGGGCAGCUGCUGGGCCAGCGCUACGGGCCCCUCUCCGAGCCAGGCAGUGCUCGUGCCUAUAGCAACAGCAUCGUCCGCAGUAGCCGCACUACUCUUGACCGCAUGGAGGACUUUGAGGAUGAUCCUCGGGCCCUGGGGGCCCGUGGGCACCGUCGUUCUGUCAGCAGAGGCUCCUACCAGCUGCAGGCGCAGAUGAACCGUGCCGUCUAUGAGGACAGGCCCCCUGGCAGCGUGGUGCCCACGUCAGCAGCAGAGGCAAGUCGGGCCAUGGCCGGGGACACGUCACUGAGCGAGAACUAUGCCUUUGCGGGCAUGUAUCAUGUUUUUGACCAGCACGUGGAUGAGGCAGUCCCAAGGGUGCGCUUCGCCAAUGAUGACCGACACCGCCUGGCCUGCUGCUCACUCGACGGCAGCAUCUCCCUGUGCCAGCUGGUGCCUGCCCCACCCACAGUGCUUCGCGUGCUACGGGGCCACACCCGUGGUGUCUCCGACUUCGCCUGGUCCCUCUCCAAUGACAUCCUCGUGUCCACCUCACUGGAUGCCACCAUGCGCAUCUGGGCCUCUGAGGAUGGUCGCUGCAUCCGAGAGAUCCCUGACCCCGAUAGCGCUGAACUGCUCUGCUGCACCUUCCAGCCUGUCAACAACAACCUCACUGUGGUGGGGAACGCCAAGCACAACGUGCAUGUCAUGAACAUCUCCACAGGCAAGAAAGUGAAGGGGGGCUCCAGCAAGCUGACAGGCCGUGUCCUUGCUCUGUCCUUUGAUGCCCCUGGCCGGCUGCUCUGGGCGGGUGAUGACCGUGGCAGUGUCUUCUCUUUCCUCUUUGAUAUGGCCACAGGGAAGCUGACCAAAGCCAAGCGUUUGGUGGUGCAUGAGGGGAGCCCUGUGACCAGCAUCUCAGCCCGGUCCUGGGUCAGCCGCGAGGCCCGGGAUCCCUCACUGCUCAUCAAUGCUUGCCUCAACAAGUUGCUGCUCUACAGGGUGGUAGACAACGAGGGGACCCUGCAGCUGAAGAGAAGCUUCCCCAUCGAGCAGAGCUCACAUCCUGUGCGCAGCAUCUUCUGUCCCCUCAUGUCCUUCCGCCAGGGGGCCUGCGUGGUGACGGGCAGUGAGGACAUGUGCGUGCACUUCUUUGAUGUGGAGCGGGCGGCCAAGGCUGCUGUCAACAAGCUGCAGGGCCACAGUGCACCUGUGCUUGAUGUCAGCUUCAACUGCGACGAGAGCCUACUGGCCUCCAGUGACGCCAGCGGCAUGGUCAUCGUCUGGAGGCGGGAGCAGAAGUAGGGUCCUGUCGGCCCUGCUGCUGUCCUCCAUCCCACCCCUCUUACUCCAGCCUCGUGUUGUAAAUAAAGUUUCGGUGGUCAUGCUGAGGGCCGGCUCCCAGCUCUGCCGGGGACGGACAGGGCAGAGGGCAGCGGGCAGCUCCAGGAACACGGUGGAACGGGGUUCAUUGACUCAUUUGUGCAUUCAUGCAUCGACGGAUUCAUUCAUUCCACAAGCAUUGAUUGAAUGUCUGCUGGGUUACAGGCCCUGCCUUAACUGUUUUACACACUUAUGCAUUCGAUAGACAUUAGUGAGCCCUGACCGUGUGCCAGGAACUGUUCUAGGCACUGGGGAUACUGCUCUGACCUAAACUGAUGGAAAUGCCUGCCUUCAUUGGGCUUGCAUCAUAGCGGAGACAGUAGAUAAAAACAUGGAACAGGCCAGCUAAUGAUGAGUGGUAUGAAGAAAAUAAAGCAAGGAUGGGAGACAGAGCUGCAGAAGUUGGGGGAGUGGGCUCUUUAUGGUGACAGCAUCAGGGAAGAUGAUCCUGACAGGGUGACUUUUUUGUUUUUGAGACAGGGUCUCACUCUGUCACCCAGGUUGGAAUGCAGUGGCAUGACCAUAGCUCACUGCAGCCUCAACCUCCAGGGCUCAAGUGAUCCUCACUUAAGCCUCCCAAGUAGCUGGGACUACAGGUGUGUGCCACCACACUCGGGUAAUUUUUGUAUUUUUAGUAGAGACGGGGUCUCGCCAUGUUGCUCAGGCUGGUCUUGAACUCCUGGGCUCAAGCGAUCCACUCGCCUCAGCCUCCCAAAGUGCUGGGAUUACAGGCAUGAACCACCACGCCUGGCUCAGGGUGACAUUUAAAGACCUGAAUGAAGUGAGUGGGAGUCAUAGUGUAGGGGGAGAACAUUCCAGGCAGAGAGAAAGCCAGCCUAAAGGCACUGAGGCUGGAGCGCUCCAGAAGGAUCAUUGUGUAUGCCAGAGUCUUGCUGGACCAGAGUGUGACAGUACAUGAGGUCAGACAGGCCAGAUGCUUCAUGGGCCACAGUUAGGACUUUGGCUUUUUUUCUGAGUGGGGGUGACCAGAAGGUGUCAAGCAGAGGAGGAACAUGAUCUGACUUGGUCAUAGAGGCUCCCUCUGGCUGCUGAAGGGGACAGAUUGGGGGUGGGGGUAGAAGCAGGGGACCCAGCAGGAGACCCCUCUGAGCGCAGUGAUGGGGACUUGCACCAGGGUAGUGACAGUGGAGGAGUUGGCGGGGGAAUGUUGGGUCGGACCCCCAGGGGGUUCACUAUGUUAGGCUGCAGGACUCUGCUGCCUCCUCAGGGGGCGAUAUUCCCAACCCUUCUGUGCAUUGUGUUGUUUAUUAAAAGCAGGGAGCAGAGGUGUUGAGUCCUGGAGCCCCAAGCUGGUGCAGGAGCAACGGGAAGUUAAGGCUGACCUGGGGCCUCCUGCUGUGUGGCGGAAUCUCCAUCCCUCAGACCACCCCUGUCUCCUCCCAGCCCCAUCCAGGGUACAAAUUCCAGCCCUGGAACAGCUCAGAGACCAAAAAGUGAUGUUAAGUAUUUGAGGGGAGCCCCAAGAGAGGAGAAAAAGCUUUGAGUAUUGAUGGGGGUAAAUAACCAAAAUCACUUAUCAGUGGCCUGCGUCACCAGAAAAUGUCAAAGUUACCUGAAGCAGCAAAGAGGCUCUUGCUCCGGCCCCUCCCUUCCUUCUCAGCUCCAUUUGUUGCCACAUAUGCGUUGACUGGAACUGCGACUGACAUCUUGGGACCUUAGGGUCAGUCCACAGCGUGGUAGAGACUCCAGCUUGGCCCAGCAUUGCUGAGCUGCUGAACUCGCACCAACAGUCUUGUUGGAGGGAAAUAAUCUCCCGUUUGUUCAGUCCAGUUAUUUGACAGUGUGGUUACUUGCACCCCAAGCAUUUCUAACUGGCACUUCCAUCUAAUAGACCUCAGGGUACAUGGUGGUGAGAUAGGGACAUCAGUGAGCUGGAUUGUUCCCAUGGUAAAGGUCAUGUAUGUGUGUGUGUGUCAUGGUCCUCAAUACCAGCCCCAAGCCCAGUGAUUUGCUAGGAGGACUCCCAAGACUCAGUAUGUGGUUGUAUUCAUGGCUACGAUUGACUUAUUACAACAAAAAGAUAUGGAGCAAAAUCAGCAAAAAGAAAUGGUGUGCAGGACCAACUCCCAGAGAGACCCAGGCACAAGUUUCCAGGGCUUCUCUCUCAUUGGAGUCACACAAGAUGUGCUCGGUUCACAGUAAUGGGUUGUGACAAUACAUGCGAAAUGUUGCUGACCAAGGAAGCUCAAUUAGAGACUCAGCACCCAGAGGUUUUUUUUGUUGUUGUUGUUGUUUUGGUUUUUUUUUGGCGGGGGGGGGGGGGUCUUGCUCUGACGCCCAGGCUGGAAUGCAGUGGCAUGAUCUUGGCUCACUGCAGCCUCCACCUCCUGGGUUCAAGCGAUCCUCGGGCCUCAGCUUCCCGAAUAGCUGGAACUACAGGCGCGCACCAGCAAGCUCGGCUAAUUUUUGUAUUUUUAGUAGGGAUGGGGUUUCACCAUGUUGGCCAGGCUGAUCUUGAACUCCUGACCUCAAGUGAUCCUCCCACCUCAGCCUCCCAAACUGCUGGGAUUACAGGCGUGAGCACCUGGCUGGUAUCAAGUUUUUAUUGGGGCAUGGUCACAUAGGCACCCCCUGCCUGGCACCUACCCAAAUCCCAGGCUCCCAAAAGGAAAGCAGGGGCUCAGCAUAAACCACCUUUUUUUUUUUUUUUUUAAUUGAGACGGAGUCUCGCUUUGUCGCCAGGCUGGAGUGCAGUGGCGUGAUCUCGGCUUACUGUAACCUCCGCCUCCUGGGUUCAAGCAAUUCUCCUGCCUCAGCUUCCUGAAUAGCUGGGACUACAGGCGCCUGCCACCACCACGCCCAGCUAAUUUUUGUAUUUUUAGUAGAGACGGGGUUUCACCAUAUUGGCCAGGCUGGUCUCCAUCUCUUGACCUUGUGAUCCGCCUGCCUCGACCUCCCAAAGUGCUGGGAUUACAGGCAUGAGCCACCGCUCCUGGCCCACUUUUUUAUACAAACAGCUUAGGUAGAGUAAGCCAUUCUUUUUUUUCUUUCUUUCUUUUUUUUUUUUUUUGAGACAGGGUCUCACUUUGUUGCCCAGGCUGGAGUGCAGUGGCUCAAACAUGGUUCGCUGCAGCCUCAACCUCCCAGGCUCAAGCGGUCCUGCUGCCUCAUCCUCCAAAGUAGCUGGGACCACAGACAUGCACCACCAUGACCCCAGCUGAUUUUUGCAGAGAUGGGUUUUGCCAUGUUGCCCAGGCUGGCCUUGAACUCCUGGGCUCAAGUGAUCCUCUCACCUUGGCCUACCAAAGUGCUGGCGUUACAGGUGUGAGCCACCACACCCGGCCCGAGUGAGCCAUUCUUAUCUCUUAGGGAAUGGUGGGAACCCUCCUGGAGUCUAUGUUCUUAGACACCACCCAAGGGCCAACCUUGAAGCAGGCCUUUCCAAGGAUCGCAGUUGAGGCCUGCUCUGUUACUGUUUUUCUGCACAGUGUGCAACACCACACAGAUGCCCAGUUUCUACCAAGGUCUGUGGAUGGCAGGAUAAUUUUGAGGAACCUCCUUUUUCGCUAACACUUUCUUCUUUUGUUUACACUCUUCACAUUGUCUAUUGAGUCUGGAUUCAAGAUGAUUGAUUGUGAAUAUUGUUGUGCAUGAUUUUGGGGGUUUCCUCCUUGUGAAAUUUUGAGGUGGCAGAUUUGACAUUCUACUUUAAACUCAUCUUGGUGGCACUUUUCUUGACUCACCACCUAAGGGGGAAUAAAUAAUGAAGAAAGAAUAAAAAUAGUGUUAUCAGUCACA